GAGGGCGGUGGCUCAGGCUCCUGGAAAGGACCGUCCACCCCUCCGCGCUGGCGGUGUGGACGCGGAACUCAGCGGAGAAACGCGAUUGAGAAAUGGAAAAGAAAAUGAAAUAAAUCAGCAGUUAUGAGGCAGAGCCUAAGAGAACUAUGGCAACAUCAGGUGACUGUCCCAGAAGUGAAUCGCAGGGAGAAGAGCCUGCUGAGUGCAGUGAGGCCGGUCUCCUGCAGGAGGGAGUACAGCCAGAGGAGUUUGUGGCCAUCGCGGACUACGCUGCCACCGAUGAGACCCAGCUCAGUUUUUUGAGAGGAGAAAAAAUUCUUAUCCUGAGACAAACCACUGCAGAUUGGUGGUGGGGUGAGCGUGCGGGCUGCUGUGGGUACAUUCCGGCAAACCAUGUGGGGAAGCACGUGGAUGAGUACGACCCCGAGGACACGUGGCAGGAUGAAGAGUACUUCGGCAGCUAUGGAACUCUGAAACUCCACUUGGAGAUGUUGGCAGACCAGCCACGAACAACUAAAUACCACAGUGUCAUCCUGCAGAAUAAAGAAUCCCUGACGGAUAAAGUCAUCCUGGACGUGGGCUGUGGGACUGGGAUCAUCAGUCUCUUCUGUGCACACUAUGCGCGGCCUAGAGCGGUGUACGCGGUGGAGGCCAGUGAGAUGGCACAGCACACGGGGCAGCUGGUCCUGCAGAACGGCUUUGCUGACAUCAUCACCGUGUACCAGCAGAAGGUGGAGGAUGUGGUGCUGCCCGAGAAGGUGGACGUGCUGGUGUCUGAGUGGAUGGGGACCUGCCUGCUGGCUGCGCCUCUCCUGAGCUGCCGCAUUCUCCCCUGCACCUGUGCGUCUGGCCCUCUUCACGUCCUCCUGGCCUGCUGUCUGCCUCUCCCCUGCACCUGUGCGUCUGUCCCUCUUCAUGUCCUCCUUGCCUGCUGUCUGCCUGUUCUCAGAGCCCCUCAGCCCUCAGGCCUUCAUCUCUCCUGGCCCAUCUUCCUACUCUGACGCUGACAUGUAGUAAAAGUCUGAAGACAGAGAAGAGUGCAUGUGCGUUUAGCAUAGGAGGGGCAGCUUUCAGUCAGUGCAGCAAGGGCAUGUAGUUGUUCAGAGAUGGUGCUGGAACGACUGAUUUGGAGAAAAGAGGCCCUUCUUCACACCAUCUGCUAAAAUAAACCUCAGAUGGGCUCAAGAGUUAAAUAUUUAAGAAAAGGAGGAAACAAAAAAAUUGCUACAAGUUUAUUUGUUGUUAGGAUGGGAAAGGUUUUUCUAAGAACCAAGUUCAUAAUGAAGCUGUCAAAUAAAAUACUUGACAAAAAAUUCCCCUUCAUACAUUAGCACAGCUAAAAACUAUUAAAUGGUAAAUGCAACUAAAGAAUUGCAGCUAAAGAAUUGUGUGACGUAAAGAGUUGCAAUAAGAAAAGCAUAAGAUAAAGGUAACCUCAUGGAAGGUGAGCAGGGACUAGAAAGGCAGAGAAAUGCCAGAGGCCAGGAGCUUGAACGUUGUUCAAUGCCACCAACAAUUUGAAAGUAACUGUAAUAGUUUUGACCUGGGAAGUUGGCUGAGCAAUCCUCUAAUAUCUGAUGCUCCCGAUGCUGAGGUUGUGGGGAAGUGUGCACCGCCAUGCCCUUUUUUUGGCAGUGUAAAUUGGUAAAGCCUUUUGAAGGAAAAUAGGGCAGAAUAAGUCAAAGAGCAUUAAAAUUUUUUUGUUUUUCCAGAAGCAGCAAAGUUCUGAAGGAGACGCAAGUAAAGAUACCACAGGUGUCCUAGAUUGUCAACAGACCAUUUAAUCAUUUUUGUUAACAAAGCAGGUGACAAUUGAGCCCUAAUUUGCGUUAUCAUUAGUUGUUACAGGAUCUUGCUUGUUCUCCUGAGGCCACGCCACGAUUUCCGAGAAGCAGGUUGCACACUCAGCAGUCUCCCACUAGCCAGUGGCACUGCAGGUGCAGGGGCUGCCUCCUGGACCUUUCAGGACGCUUUGCAAGGUCACUGAGGAUCUCCAUUGCACAUUUGGUAGAAUUAAAAGACUGCCAGACUCAGUCUUACUGUUGUUAGUGUAUUCGUGCUGUCAAUAUGUGAUGAGGACAUAUUAUAUUCCGUUAUUCUCUUUAGCUCAAGGAAGAAUAAAGAAUUUGGACCAAAAUUACAACCACAUUAUGACGAAUUUUCUAAGCAAAAGAAACAAAGUAACUGCUGAGGUUAACAAAGAUGUAAUAAUUCUCUUCACACAGCCUUGUACUGUUUUAUUGACUGUAUUAUCACAAAUCCUGAGCUUAACGAAAGUCUUUAUAAGUCAGCUCAUGAAAACAGGCACGUGGCCAGUAAGAAUUUAAUUUCAUACCAAUAACACUUCAGACUUCGGAUGUAUUUAAGGCUGUUUGCACAUAUUUAUAGAAUGUGUGGUGUAGAUGAUGGGACAGCUCCCCCUCAGCAAGACUCUGGCCUAAAUGUAUUUGCUUUAUUUACACAACAAGAGGAUAAGCGUAAACACGGGCACUUUCAGUUUGUGGCACUGAAGGACGAUCUACACAGGGCACCCUGCAGAGGCCACAACCAAGGCCGCCUGGCUUCCCAGUGGGACAGGCCUAAGGGAGGACUUCUGGCCCCUUUGCUUGAUGUUCAUGUUUUAUGCCUUGAUAUUUCUUUUUGGUUGCAUUCCCUGGAGCUCAUGUAGAUCAUUUUACUUUUCAGAGGUGCUAGUUCUGGUGCCCACACGCACACACACAAAACCAUCAACUCUUCUGGAUUCCUUGGUUUUAAAGCUUGCCUCAUACAAAGUACAGAGACAUCUUUUUCAGGAAACAUUGCCACCACAUGCUUGAAGGACCGCUUAUGGCUACACUUAGACAUCUCCAACCAAGGUCUCUUCACCUCCUUCUACAACAAUGCACUUUGUCUGCACUGGGACAAAAAAUGACAGCCUUUUUUCUUUUCUUGUUUUUUUUUUUUUUUGGCGUGGAGCAUUUCCGAACUUUCACGUCAUAAAAAAUGCAGCAUAGUUAAUCAGCAGCUUGCACUUCUGAGGGCACAUUCACCUCGGGGGAGGAGGAAGGAGGAGGAGCUGGUGGGUGCUGAGACUGCAGUGUCCUCCUUCCCAGCAGCUGGACCCAGAGACCAGGCACCAAAUUUUUUUGAUGAAAUUAUCCUAAGGAAAUAAUCAAAUUUGUACAGAAAUUUAUGUUAAAAAAUGUUCAUGGCAGCACCGUUUAAAAUGGGGAGAAAAUUGGAAACAACAGAAUUGUAGCAAUACAUAUGAUCAUUAAAAAUUAUGUUUUAGAAAGAUUUUUAACAGUCUUUGGAAAAAGUUGGUGACAUGUUGCUAGUUUUUAAAAAAAGUACAGAGUAUGUACAGUAUGAUUCCAAUUUUGUGUUUAAAAAUUAGACAUAGUGGUAACCUAGCUUCAGUUCCAGAUAAGAUGGAGAAGGCAUACUCCUUUCAUGUCUCCCACUGAAUGCAGCUAUAAAUCCUGGAGAGUAGACAGGGAGAAACUAUUUGAGGACUCUGGAACAAAGACAUAGUAGCAAUCGACUGGUGAAGAAGACAAGAAUUUGAAGUACGGUCAAGUAUCUGUGGGCUCCACAUCUGUAGAUACAACCUACAUGUAUUGAAAAUAUCAGAAAAUAAAAAUAACAAUACAACAAUAAACAUCAAUACAAAUAACACACCAAUACAGUAUAGCAGCUACUUACAUAACACUGACAUUGUAUUAGGUAGAAGUAAUCUAGAGAUGAUUUAAAGUCUGUCGGAGGAUGUGUGUAGCCUGUAUGUAAAAACCACGUUAUUUUAUAUGGGGGACUUUAGCAUCCAAGGAUUUGAAUAUCCACGGGGGUCCUGGAACAAGUUCCCCAUAGACACCAAGAAACAACUGUAUUCCUGAAACAGUCUUGAGUUAUCAUUUUCUUUCUUCUCCCUCUAUGUAUGUACAUAGAGUGUACAUACAUAGAGUGAGAAGCAAAGAAGGUCCAUGAAAUGGACCAAUUCUUUUGAAAACUGCAAAUUACCACAGUUCAUCUAACAUGAAAUAGAUAACCUGAAUGGUCCAAUAACUAGUAAAGAUAUUGAAUUAAUAGUUUAAAAACCUUCUGAAAGGUAAAUCU